AUUUUGGGCUUCGCUUCCACCGCACCAGCCGGCCUACCCAGUCCUUCCGGUAUCGCGUUGCUCAGGGGCUUUUCAACCCUCUGUCAGUCGGAAAACCAUCGCCGAGGCCGUGGGGGGACUCCUAUCCAUGGUGUUGAAGCGUCGAGCCGACUAGGGAACCUCCUUCCCCGCCAGGAUGGAAGUCGCAUCAGUCGCCGCCUAUUGCGCGGGCUGUUCUUCCCUGUGUUCUGCCGCCCGCUGCCGCAUUCGCUGCCCUCUGUGGCUUUUCUGCUGGCUCGAAGAUCGGCCUGGAGCAGCGACGCCACCGCUGGGCAAGGCCGAGACUCUGUAGGCUUCCUCCGAAUCCCGUCGACCUCCAGCCGCUGAGCGCCGCGGCCCUACCUGAGAGACUGUCAAGAAAAAGGAGAUGGAGCCGGGGACAGGCGGAUCGCGGAAACGGCUUGGCCCUCGGGCGGGCUUCCGGUUCUGGCCACCCUUUUUCCCUCGGCGAUCGCAAGCAGGCUCUUCUAAGUUCCCGACGCCUCUUGGCCCGGAAAACUCCGGGAACCCCACACUGCUUUCCUCUGCCCAGCCCGAGACUCGGGUCAGUUACUGGACGAAACUGCUCUCCCAGCUCCUUGCGCCGCUCCCCGGAUUGCUUCAGAAGGUGCUAAUUUGGAGCCAACUUUUCGGUGGAAUGUUUCCGACCAGAUGGCUAGAUUUUGCUGGAGUCUACAGCGCCCUGAGAGCCCUGAAGGGACGGGAGAAACCAGCCGCCCCCACAGCGCAGAAAUCUUUGAGUUCGCUGCAGCUCGACUCCUCAGACCCCUCGGUCACCAGUCCCCUUGAUUGGCUAGAGGAGGGGAUCCACUGGCAAUACUCGCCCCCAGACCUAAAAUUGGAGCUUAAGGCCAAGGGAAGUGCUUUGGACCCUGCAGCACAGGCUUUUCUCUUAGAGCAGCAGCUGUGGGGAGUGGAGCUGUUGCCCAGUAGCCUUCAAUCCCGUCUGUACUCUAACCGGGAACUUGGCUCUUCGCCCUCUGGGCCUCUAAACAUUCAACGCAUAGACAAUUUCAGUGUGGUAUCCUAUUUGCUGAACCCUUCCUACCUGGACUGCUUUCCUAGGCUAGAAGUCAGCUAUCAGAACAGUGAUGGAAAUAGCGAGGUAGUCGGCUUCCAGACACUAACCCCAGAGAGCAGCUGCCUGAGAGAGGACCAUUGUCAUCCCCAGCCGCUGAGUGCAGAACUCAUUCCGGCCUCGUGGCAGGGAUGUCCACCUCUUUCUACGGAAGGCCUACCAGAAAUUCACCAUCUUCGCAUGAAACGGCUGGAAUUCCUUCAACAGGCUAGCAAGGGGCAAGAUUUACCCACCCCUGACCAGGAUAAUGGCUACCACAGCCUGGAGGAGGAACACAGCCUUCUCCGGAUGGAUCCAAAACACUGCAGAGAUAACCCAACACAGUUUGUUCCUGCUGCUGGAGACAUUCCUGGAAACACCCAGGAAUCCACUGAAGAAAAAAUAGAAUUAUUAACUACAGAGGUUCCACUUGCUUUGGAAGAAGAGAGCCCUUCUGAGGGCUGUCCAUCUAGUGAGAUACCUAUGGAAAAGGAGCCUGGAGAGGGCCGAAUAAGUGUAGUUGAUUACUCAUACCUAGAAGGUGACCUUCCCAUUUCUGCCAGACCAGCUUGUAGUAACAAACUGAUAGAUUAUAUUUUGGGAGGUGCAUCCAGUGACCUGGAAACAAGUUCUGAUCCAGAAGGUGAGGAUUGGGAUGAGGAAGCUGAGGAUGAUGGUUUUGAUAGUGAUAGCUCACUGUCAGACUCAGACCUUGAACAAGACCCUGAAGGGCUUCACCUUUGGAACUCUUUCUGCAGUGUAGAUCCUUAUAAUCCCCAGAACUUUACAGCAACAAUUCAGACUGCUGCCAGAAUUGUUCCUGAAGAGCCUUCUGAUUCAGAGAAGGAUUUGUCUGGCAAGUCUGAUCUAGAGAAUUCCUCCCAGUCUGGAAGCCUUCCUGAGACCCCUGAGCAUAGUUCUGGGGAGGAAGAUGACUGGGAAUCUAGUGCAGAUGAAGCAGAGAGUCUCAAACUGUGGAACUCAUUCUGUAAUUCUGAUGACCCCUACAACCCUUUAAAUUUUAAGGCUCCUUUUCAAACAUCAGGGGAAAAUGAGAAAGGCUGUCGUGACUCAAAGACCCCAUCUGAGUCCAUUGUGGCCAUUUCUGAGUGUCACACCUUACUUUCUUGUAAGGUGCAGCUGUUGGGGAGCCAAGAAAGUGAAUGUCCAGACUCGGUACAGCGUGACGUUCUUUCUGGAGGAAGACACACACAUGUCAAAAGAAAAAAGAUCCCUACCAAGAAGAAGGAUGAAGAACUUAAUAGCAAAAGAAGAGCACAAUUGCCAGAGAUGCGAGAAGAAAGGACCUCACACGGUUCUUGACUUUUCUACAGAGCUCACUGCACAUUUUCCCACUAAAAUGUUGGACAGGGUUCCACUCCCAUCACCCAGACUGGAGUGCAAUGGUGCAAUCUUGGUGCUGAACCUCCGCCUCCCAGGCUCCAGCGAUUCUCCUGCCUUAGCCUCCUAAGUAGCUGGGACUACAGGCAGAUGCCAUCACACCCAGCUAACUUUAAUUUUUUUGUAGAGAUGGGGUUUCACCAUGUUGCCCAGGCUGGUCUCGAACUCUUGGGCUCAUGAGCUGCCUGCCUUGGCCUCCCAAAAUGCUGGGAUUAUAGGCGUGAGCCACCACGCCUGGACUCUUUUUUUUAAUAUAUAUAAAUAGAGAUGGGGUCUGGCUAUGUUGCCCAUAUAGCAACUCCUGGCCUCAAGCAGUCCUCCUGCCUUGGCCUCCCAAAGUGCUGGGAUUACAUGUGUGAGCCACUGGGCCUGGCCAAGUUAAUAGCUUUCCCAAAGUCACCUCUCUUAUCAGCUUUAUUGAAGUUUCAUCCACACAGCCUUGUCUGACCAGAAACAAGUGUGCCACAAUCAUCAGAUGAUGUAGAAUCACAGAAUUUAAAUGUCCUUAGAGAAAAGCUACCGUAAGCUUUAACUAAAUUUGUAGAAAGUAAUUACAAAUUUCAAUUUGGCUAGGUAUACCACAUCCAUUAAUUCUAGUGUCAUUAUUAAUAUAAGACACAUUGUUAAUUUAUGAAUUUAAUAUGCGAGCAAAUCAACUGAGACCCUCCUUUCCCAGAAUUAAUAGGCUGCAUUGGAGUACCAGAGUAUUCUUGCCACCACACCAGGGGUUUUAGCUCUUUGGCAGAAGAUUGGCUUUGGGUUUCUAGUGAUGCUCUGUUGUCUCCACCAGAUGGCGUUAUCUUCCAUCUGGGAGUGCCUGAUGGACACCUGUUAUUACAGAUCUGGUUGCUAUUGCUCCCCUGGAGGUGGGUCCCUCAAUGUGUAAACAAGCUGGAAAACUGCCCUGCCCUGCCCAUUCCAGGCCUGCCUGGCCCAGUGUGACUCCACCUUUUUGUGGUAAUUACCCAGAAGUAGGGGCUCUUUCUUAUAGGAGAACCAAGAUUUGUAUUUGAACACAAACAAAGGAACUGAUUUUUUUUUUGAGUCUUGCUGUCGCCCAGGCCUAGGCUGGAGUACAGUGGCACGGUCAUAGCUCACUGCAGCCUCCAACUUUUGGGCUUAAACAAUCCUCCCACCUCAGCCUCCCAAGUAGCUAGGACCACAGGCAUGCACCACAUUGCCUGGCUAAUUUUAUUAUUUUUGUGUGUAGAGAUGGGGUCUAAUUAUAUUGCCUAGGCUGGUCUCAAACUCCUGGCUUCAAGAGAUCCUACUGCCUGGGGCUCCCAAAGUGUCGCGAUUACAGGCAUGAGCCACCUCACUUGGCCCUUGUAUACUUUUUUAUCACUGUUCAAGUCACAUUGAAUUUUAAUUGUGAUUUGCUCUUUCCUUUCUUCCUCUGUGGUGGAAGGGUCUGCGCAGUGACCAGAGUAUUUUAGACACAUGAUACACUUUUCUUUAACUCAAGUGGUAAUUUCCAUAGCCUCUUUUUUCCAACACACAGGCUCCCUCCCGACAUAACAAGUAAUUUAUGAAUUCAUUUCAAAGAAGCAAUUUUGUAUGUGAAAAGGUCUAUCUUCAAUGUUUACAUUAUUUUGUAUUUGUAGUAUUUGAUUUUUUUUUUUUUGAAAAGCUAGCAUUAUUAGUGAUGACCUGAAACCCAAAGUUUUAAAUCAGUUGAUGUAAGGUCGUCAUGACUACUCUUUCCAGUGGUAGCCUAAGGUUCGCUGAAACAUUGUCAUCGUUAUGAAAGGCACUUCAUUAUGCAGGAUACCAUUCAUAUCCAGUUUUCUAAGAUGGUUGAGGACAUUGUUUUUUAAACUUUUCUGUUUUUUAAAUUGACAAAAAUUGUAUAUGUUUACUGUCUACAACAUGAUGUUUUGAAAUAUGUGUACAUUGUGGAAUGGUAAGUCAAGCUAAUUAACAUGUAUUACCUCACAUACUUAGCAUUUUUUUUGUGGUAAGAACCCUUAAAAUCUACUCUUAGCAAUUUCCUUUUUCUAUUUAUUUAUUUAUUUGAGACAAGCUGGAGUGCAGUGGUGCAAUUUCGCCUCACUGUAACCUCCGCGUCCUGGGCUCAAGCAAUUCUCAUGUCUCAGCCUCCCAAGUAGCUGGGACUACAGGCGCGUGCCACCACACCCGGCUAAUUUUUUGUAUUUUAGUAGAGACAGGUUUCACCCCAUGUUGCCCAGGGUGGUCUCGUACUCCUGAGCUCAGGUGAUCUGCCUGCCUUGGCCUUCCAAAGUGCUGGGAUUACAGGCGUGAGCCAUCACGCCUGGGCUUUUUAUUUAUUUAUUUUAUUUUAUUUUAUUAUUUAUUUAUGUAUUUAUUUAUUUUGAGACAGAACCUUGCUCUGUUGCCAAGCUGGAGUGCAGUGGCAUGAUCAUGGCUUUCUUCAGCCUCAACCUCCUGGGCUCAGGCAAUCCUCUUGCCUCAGUUUCCCGAGUAGCUGGGACCACAGGCUCACACCACCACAACAGGCUAAUUUUUAAGUUAUCUGUAGGGGCGAGAUCUCCCUAUAUUGCCCAGGCUGGUCUUGAAGUCCUAGGCUUAAGUGUUCCUCCUGCCUCCCAAAGUGUUGAGAUUACAGGUGUGAGCCACCUCACCUGGCCAAUUUGCAAGAAUAUAAUACAUUGUUAUUGACUAUGGUCACCAUGUCGUACAGUAGAUCUCUUGAACUUAUUCCUCCUCACUGAAAGUUUGUAUCCUUUGAGCAACGUCUCCCCAACCCACUUCUUGUUUUUUAUUAACUUAUUAAAGUAUAAUUUACAAUAAGUUUCACUCAUUUUAAGUAUGAAUUCAAUGAGUUUUGAUAAACACGUGUAGUCAUAUAAACACCACCACUAUCAAAAUAUGGAUCAUUUCCAUCACCCAGAAAGUUCCCUUAUGUUCUUUUGUAUUCGGUCCCCUUCCCAACCUCCAGCUUUUGGCAGCCAUUGCUUUUCUUUUCUUUGUCUUUUUUUUUUUUUUUGACAGACAGGGUCUUACUGUCACCCAGGCUGGAGUGUAGUGGUGUGAUCACGGCUCACUGCAGCCUUAUCUCCCUGGGUUCAGGUGAUCCUCCCACCUCAGCCUCCUGAGUAGCUGGGACUACAGCUGUGUGCGACCACACCCAGCUGGUUUUUUGUUUUUUUUUUUUUGUUUUUGUUUUUGCUUUUUUUUUUUUUUUUGUAUUUUUAGUAGAGAUAAGGUUUUGGCAUGUUGCCCAGGCUAGUCUUGAACUUCUGGGCUCAAGAGAUCUGCCUGUUUUGGCCUCCCAACAUGCUGGGAUUGCAGGUGUGAGCCACCACGUCUGGCCUUUGAUCUGCUUUCAACACUUUUAGCUCUUCUAGAAUUUCAGAAAAAUGGUAUCGGAUGUACAGCAUGGACCCUUCUGUGGUGGGCUUCUUUACUGUAAUGCUUUUGAGAUUCAUCUGUGCUGUUGAGUGUCUCUGCAGUCCAUUCCUUCUGUUGAGUGUAUCAGUAGUCCAUUCCUUUUCAUGGCUGAGUAGUAUUUCAUUGUAUAAUUAUACCACUAUUUGUUCAUUUACUAGAUAAUAAACAGUUGGCUUGUUUAAGUAUGAAUUCAAUGAGUUUUGAUAAAUAUGUGUAGUUAUAUAAACAUGACUACAUAUAUAAACAUAUAAACAUAUACAUAUAUAAGCACAUAUAAAUUUGUGUCUAUUAUGAAUAAAGCUUCUAUGAACUGUUGAGUACAA